GGCUCUGUGACUGAGGCGGCGGCGGUGGCGGCCAAGCGGGAUACGGGCGGCGGGAGCUGGGGAACAGGCAUGGACGUUUCCGGGCAAGAGACCGACUGGCGGAGCACCGCCUUCCGGCAGAAGCUGGUCAGUCAAAUCGAGGAUGCCAUGAGGAAAGCUGGUGUGGCACACAGUAAAUCCAGCAAGGAUAUGGAGAGCCAUGUUUUCCUGAAGGCCAAGACCCGGGACGAAUACCUUUCUCUCGUGGCCAGGCUCAUUAUCCAUUUUCGAGACAUUCAUAACAAGAAAUCUCAAGCUUCCGUCAGUGAUCCUAUGAAUGCACUCCAGAGCCUGACUGGCGGACCUGCUGCGGGAGCCGCUGGAAUUGGCAUGCCUCCUCGGGGCCCGGGACAGUCUCUGGGCGGGAUGGGUAGCCUUGGUGCCAUGGGACAGCCAAUGUCUCUCUCAGGGCAGCCGCCUCCUGGGACCUCGGGGAUGGCCCCUCACAGCAUGGCUGUCGUGUCUACGGCAACUCCACAGACCCAGCUGCAGCUCCAGCAGGUGGCGCUGCAGCAGCAGCAGCAACAGCAGCAGUUCCAGCAGCAGCAGCAGGCGGCGCUACAGCAGCAGCAGCAGCAGCAGCAACAGCAGCAGUUCCAGGCUCAGCAGAGUGCCAUGCAGCAGCAGUUCCAAGCAGUAGUGCAGCAGCAGCAGCAGCUCCAGCAGCAGCAGCAGCAGCAGCAGCAUCUAAUUAAAUUGCAUCAUCAAAAUCAGCAACAGAUACAGCAGCAGCAACAGCAGCUGCAGCGAAUAGCACAGCUGCAGCUCCAACAACAGCAACAGCAGCAGCAGCAGCAGCAGCAGCAGCAGCAGCAGGCUUUGCAGGCCCAGCCACCAAUUCAGCAGCCACCGAUGCAGCAGCCACAGCCUCCGCCCUCCCAGGCUCUGCCCCAGCAGCUGCAGCAGAUGCAUCACACACAGCACCACCAGCCGCCACCACAGCCCCAGCAGCCUCCAGUUGCUCAGAACCAACCAUCACAACUCCCGCCACAGUCGCAGACCCAGCCUUUGGUGUCACAGGCGCAAGCUCUCCCUGGACAAAUGUUGUAUACCCAACCACCACUGAAAUUUGUCCGAGCUCCGAUGGUGGUGCAGCAGCCCCCAGUGCAGCCCCAGGUGCAGCAGCAGCAGACAGCAGUACAGACAGCUCAGGCUGCCCAGAUGGUGGCUCCCGGAGUCCAGGUGGAGGUCCCCGCCCGACUGGCACAGGAAGGAGGAUGGAGAGUGGUUACCACUGUGGUUCGUUGCUGAUGACACAUAUCUUGAUGUCUUAGAUUGUUCCUGGAGCUGAUGGAGGUGAGUGAAUGGUUCACUUUGAGGGCCUUCAGAUCUGAUCAGCCACCCUCUAACCAGGAGGUCAGAGAUGCAGAUUGGAGCUCCCCUUGUGUUGUUCACACAGUGGACAUCAGGACGUGGUGACCACGUGUUGCAGCUUUGUAUGUAUGAGCUGCCGCGUGCUGCGGAAACAGGCCUCUUGAGUUCAUGAAUGAAAUUCUGGGAUUGGGGGCCCCCAUGCAGGCAGCCCUCCAUGCCCUGUCUCUCAAGCCCAUCUUAGAGCCGAAGAGAGGCGCCCUGUCAGGCCCUUGCAGUACUGUGGUGUUGGAUGUGGUAAAGGGUAGCCUGGGACUGAGUAUUCUAGAAAAAUUGCUCAGCCUUGUGCUGUGCACACCUGGUUCUCUUUCCAGUGUUAUUUAUGUAGCUGAGAAGGGCAAUGUCACCCACAAGGGGAUUUAGCAGGACACAGCAGACUUCUUUUUCUCCCCUAUAAAACCAAGACAUGCAGGCACAGUGGCUCAUGCCUGUAAUCCCAACGUUUUGGGAAGCCAAGGUGAGAGGAUCACUUGAGACCAGGAGUUCAAAACUAUCCUGGGCAACACAGCGAGACCCUGUCUCUACAAAAAAAUAAAAAUAAAAAGUUAGCUGGGCGGAGUGGUGCGUGUCUGCAGUCCCUGCUACUCGGGAGGCCGAGUUGGGAGGAUCGUGCAAGCCCAGGGGUUUGAGGCUGCAGUGAGCUGUGAUGACAGCAUUACACUCUAGCCUGGGAGACAGAGCAAAACUCUUGUCUCUUUAAAAAAGCAAGAAACAGGACAGAAUGCAUCUCAUUUUCUUUUUUUUUUUUUUUUUAAAGACAGAGUCUCUUGCUCUGUCACCCAGGCUGGAGUGCAAUGGUACAGUCUCAGCUCACUGCAGUCUCCACCUCCUGGGUUCAAGGGAUUCUCCUGCCUCAGCCUCCCAAGUACCUGGGAUUACAGGCAUGUGCCACCAUGCCUGGCUAAUUUUGUAUUUUUAGUAGAGACGGGGUUUUGUCAUGUUGGCCAGGCUGGUCUUGAACUCCUCGCCUUAAGAGAUGUGCCCGCUUUGGCCUCCCAAAGUGCUGGAAUUACAGGCGUAAGCCACUGUGCCUGGCCAUGCAUCUCAUUUUCAAACAGUCCCUAUACCUUUGUCAUUUAACGUUCUAUUCUUUUAGUAUGUGAAAACCAAACUCUAAUUUACAAGUCACAAAGAAUUAUCCAAGACAGACUCCCAUUGUGGACAUGUAUGUGGCAUUGCUGAUUCACAGCUACUGUACUGAAGCCUUGGCCACCCUGGAGGACCCUCUCUCUUUUUGCUGGACCCUUCUGCACAGUGACUGCAGUAGGGAGAGUCAGACCUGGGGGUGGGGGAGAGGUUUUUUGGAUUCCUCUCUGGGUAGAUGUGUGUUGGGAAGUAGUGAAAUGUUGAUAGCUGCCUGGCUCAUCUGAUCCAGUAAACAUAACUGGUGCGUUUGGGUUGAAAGAAAUUGGGCUUUCCUUAUCAGUUCUCAGUUAUAAGAACAUCAGUCAGCAGUACAUUAGACUUAAGCUUUGCAUUCCUUGCGUUUUUUUGUUUGUUUUUCUCUUCCUGGAAAAAAGUUUGCUUCUCUCAUACCAUCUGACUUACUUCCAGGCUUUUCUCCCUUGUGGAACGAGUGCCGUUGAGCCCUGCUGCACUCUCAGACGGGCUCCUCCGAAGUGCCGCAGGUGGUGGUAAAUCGACUCUCACCCACUGGGGUCGCUCCUUCGUGUCUCCCCCCGGUCGGUUCAUCUGUUGCUCUGGCUGCAGGAGGAACGAGUGAGCUUCUGGUCGGCGUCUGCCAUGCCGUGUCACCCCGGCUUCUGGCACCUCCUGUGCGUGCCCAGGAUUGUGAAUGUGGGCCGUGUGUGUGAGGCCACGGGUCUCCCUGCAGCCACUCUCCUGCUGGAGCUCUGUUACUGGCACCUGUCGCUGCCUGCACCGAAGGCUGGCAGCACCUCCUGGAGCUUGGGACCCAGAGCACAGCCUCCCACCAUGAGAUGUGUUGUUUUUCUGUGGAUCAGUCCUCCUUUCUUUCUGAGCCUGGCGUGUUUUGUUCUAGUUUGUUACCGUCCUAAGUGCCUGUAGGCCCUGCUCUCCAGGGACGAGACUCGGGCUCUACCCCCAACUCAGAACCCAGAGCAAGAGUGGUCGGGCCCGGGCCCACAACAGUGCUCAGCUGUCCUGCUGCCUUUGUAGUUCAAGAAGUGUCCAUUGAUGAGGGGAAUGGUCCUGGCUCAUGCUGGAGUUCCUGACUCGCAUCCCUGUGGAGAUGAACUUCCUCGUCAGGGCGGAGGCCUGCCAAGCAGUCCCCCCAGGCUUCUCUUGCUCACCUUUGCCCAUUUUUAUUACGAAAGAAAACCAGUUCCUUGAUAGAUACCAGGACCAUCAGCCUCAGGCCUGGAGGAGGAGAGGAGGAUGAUUUGGGUUCGGGCUGUAAGAGGUGUGCCACUGAGAAGGAGGGAUGCUGUGAGCAGGCUUAACUGAGCUCAUGGUUCAGUGGGAGUUGAGUGUUCUCAUCACAGGCUUUGGUGGAAUGUACUCUUGACAUCUGUCCCCAGGAGCCUGGUCUCCAGAAACACCAGCUCAGGCCCUCAAGGUCUGGCUCUGAUGGUUCUGUGGGCUAUAGGAUUCUGAUCUGUUAGCGAGGUGUGUUCAGAAGUGUGUUGAGGACACCAGUGCAGGAGAGCAACCAGUAGAACAGAAAGGUCUGGAAGCAGCAUUCUUGGCAAAUCUUCUAGAUUCCCAAUGCCCAGACAGACCUGGAGGUGCUGUGGGCUUGAACAUGUGGGUGGCCUCCCCUCCCAGGCUGCCCCGAGCUGCCCAAGCUUUCCUUGCCCUGGUGCUCCUUCUUGCAGAGGCUACACGUGCCCUCUCCACCUGCCCAGGCACUGAGUUUCUUUGUUGCGAUCACCUUGUCUGUUGUCCCUCUGUCCUCAAAGAUGAUCACGGAAGCCUUGGCCCAAGGUGGGAUGCACAUAAGAGCCCGGUUCCCGCCUACCACCGCUGUGUCCGCCAUCCCGUCAAGCUCCAUCCCUUUGGGCAGACAGCCCAUGGCACAG